AGCUCCCCGCCGGGCUCGCGCCGCAGAGGCCGGUGAGGCGCCGGCGGCCACGCCGCGGAAGGCGCGGGCCGAGCAGAGCCGGGCGUUGGAGCCCGCGCGCGCAUGGAGGCGUUGCCGGCAGCCCCCUGAGGGCAGCGGGGAGACAAGACCCGGCGACCUCGCGCAUCCCUCGAGCCGCCACGCGCUCUCGCCACCGGGCGGCGACGGGCCGCGGAGCCGGCGCGGCCAUGGCGACGGGCGGCCAGCAGAAGGAGAACACGCUGCUUCACCUCUUCGCCGGCGGGUGUGGAGGCACAGUUGGUGCUAUUUUCACUUGUCCACUAGAAGUCAUUAAGACACGGUUGCAGUCUUCAAGAUUAGCUCUCCGGACAGUCUACUAUCCUCAGGUUCAUCUGGGGACCAUUAGUGGAGCUGGAAUGGUGAGACCAACAUCCGUGACACCUGGACUCUUUCAGGUUCUGAAGUCGAUCUUGGAGAAAGAGGGACCAAAGUCACUUUUUAGAGGCUUGGGUCCAAAUUUGGUUGGAGUUGCACCAUCAAGGGCUGUAUACUUUGCAUGUUACUCCAAAGCCAAAGAGCAAUUUAAUGGCAUUUUCGUGCCUAACAGCAAUAUUGUGCAUAUUUUCUCAGCUGGCUCUGCAGCUUUUAUCACAAAUUCCUUAAUGAAUCCUAUAUGGAUGGUUAAAACCCGAAUGCAGCUAGAACAGAAAGUGAGGGGCUCUAAGCAGAUGAAUACACUCCAGUGUGCUCGUUACGUUUACCAGACCGAAGGCAUUCGUGGCUUCUAUAGAGGAUUAACUGCCUCGUAUGCUGGAAUUUCCGAAACUAUAAUCUGCUUUGCUAUUUAUGAAAGUUUAAAGAAGUAUCUGAAAGAAGCUCCAUUAGCCUCUUCUGCAAAUGGGACUGAGAAAAAUUCCACAAGUUUUUUUGGACUUAUGGCAGCUGCUGCUCUUUCUAAGGGCUGUGCCUCCUGCAUUGCUUAUCCACACGAAGUCAUAAGGACGAGGCUCCGGGAAGAGGGCACCAAGUACAAGUCUUUUGUCCAGACGGCGCGCCUGGUGUUCCGGGAAGAAGGCUACCUUGCCUUUUAUAGAGGACUGUUUGCCCAGCUUAUCCGGCAGAUCCCAAAUACUGCCAUUGUGUUGUCUACUUAUGAGUUAAUUGUGUACCUGUUAGAAGACCGUACUCAGUAACAGGCCGGAAAAUUGUGCUCUAGAAGAAUAAAACUGAAAAACUCUAGAGAAUUUUUUUUCCCCAUUGAUGUUUAGAAAGUUUGAGACUGAAACAGGAAAGGCCAUAAAAUAUCUGGUUCAUAUCACCUGUUGGACAUUUCCUUUUGGAUUCAUGCUUUCUGGAAGGUUUAAAUUCAUUAACGUUAAUAGUUAAUUAUAACUUUUUUUUUAACUUAAGAGGAUUCAGGGUUAAGCACCAACUAAAUUAAAUCAUGCUAUUUAAUUUAAGUAUACAUUUGGCUUGUGUCCUCUUUUAUGCUCACUAUACUAUGAAGGACUUAAGUAAUUCAGAUAAACCUGCCCUAGAACUGCAGAGAAAAAUGAUAAAGUGAGAAUACAACUUGUUUUAUAAUCUGACUUUAAGAUCUUGCACUGCUAGACAGGGAAGAAGUGUCGCAUUUUGGCUGGGCACUGUGGCUCACGCCCGUAAUCCCAGCACUUUGGGAGGCCGAGGCAGAUGGAUCACGUGAAGUCAGGAGUUCCAGACCAGCCUGGCCAACAUGGCGAAACCCUGUCUCUACUAAAAAUACAAAAAUUAGCCGGACGUGUGCCUGUAAUCCCAGCUACUUGGGAGGCUGAGGCAGGAGAAUCACUUGAAACCCAGGGGGCAGAGGUUGCAGCGAGCUGAGAUCACGUCACUUCACUCCAGCCUGGUCGACAGAGUGAGACUCCAUCUCAAAAAAAAAAAAAUUGUGUCACAUUUUGGUGGUGGUGUGUGGACCAGGACAAACUUCCCAGCAAUUUUUCUUCUUUGUACAUUUCCAAUUACUUGCAGAUUGAUCAUCUAAGCGUUCAGACUGCUGAGAUGAAUAUAUAUAACUUUCUGAGACUCAAUAUUUUAAGCUAUAAAAAACUUCCUGAAGUUAUCCUUUUCUCCCUACUUUGAACCAAAGGCAAGAAUUUUUAAAGAACUGUUUUAUCAAUGGCCUGGCUCCUGGAUAUAGUUCCGGAAGUUAAGACCAGUUGCCUUGUUAAGUGUGUUGACAGCACAGCUACCCUGUUUGGCUGUGAAUCCAGAAUGUGAUGAAGAACAGUCAUUCCCACUGAGGUCUUUAGCCCUGUUCUUGGACCUCUGCUCUUGCAGAAAAGGAGCACAACGUAGGACUAUGGCUCACCCGUCAGAGAGCUCACAUUCUGAUAGAAAGCACUGGGAUUGUUUAAAUAUCCUAGUUCAACAUUAAAAAAAAAAAAAAUUUAAUCCCAGCACUUUGGGAGGCCAAGGCGGGCAGAUCACGAGGUCAGGAGAUCGAGACCAUCCUGGCUAACACGGUGAAACCCCGUCUCUACUAAAAAAAUACAAAAAAAUUGGCCAUGCGUGGUGGCGGGCACCCAUAGUCCCAGCUACUCGGGAGGCUGAGGCAGGAGAAUGGCGUGAACCUGGGAGGCGGAGCUUGCAGUGAGCUGAGAUGGCGCCACUGCACUCCAGCCUGGGCCACAGAGUGCGACUCCAUCUCAAAAAAAAAAAAAAAACCAGGAUGUUACCCCCUUGGUUUUAAAGCAAAUUUAAUAAGGGAACAAAAAGAUGAUACUAAGAAGAAGGCAAGUAAAACCCCUAGUCUUCCAUUAGCUCUUUCACUGGAAUUUGAGUAUAUUGUACAUGAAGGUUGGUUUUCAAUUUGAACGUCUAGAAAGAUACUCAUUUCUAAUACCUAUGCACUGUAGUUUCAGGUUUACUUGCAGACACCCUGGUAGGGUUAAGAGGAGGAUAUUUCCAAGUUAUUUUAAAUUGAGUUUACUUUUAACUGGGGUUCUUGACUCUAGUGUAAUUGCUCCAACAACUACGUAGAAGUCAAAAUGAGUGACUUUAGUGAAGCUUCUGUACUUUACAAUACAUGACAGUAAUGCUAUUCCAGAAGUUUUGUUUUGUUUUGUUUUGAGAUGGAGUCUCGCUCUGUCUCUCCCAGGCUGGAGUGCAGUGGCACAAUCUCGGCUCACUACAGCCUCCACCUCCCGGUUUCAAGCAAUUCUCCUGUCUUAGCCUCCUGAGUAGCUGGGACUACAGGCAUGCGCCACCACACCUGGCUAAUUUUGUAUUUUUAGUAGAGAUGGGGUUUCACCAUGUUGGCCAGGCUGGUCUCAAACUCUUGACCUCAGGUGAUCUACCCGCCUCGGCCUCCCAAAGUACUGGGAUUACAGGAGGGAGCCACCAUACCUGGCCCGCGCCGCCCCUUCCUUUGUUGUUAUUGUUGUUUUGAGACAAGGUAUCACUCGAUCACUGAAGCUGGAUACAGUGGCAAGAUCAUAGCUCACUGUAACCUCAAACUCCUGGGCACAAGGGAUCCUCGCAUCUCAGCCUCCCAAGUAGCUUGGACCACAGGAAAGUACCACCAUGCCCAGCUAAUGUUUUUUCAUUUUUUGUGCAGACGAGGUUUUGCUAUGUUGUCCAGGCUGGUCUCAGACUACUGGCCAGAAGCGAUCUUACCUCCUCAGCCUCCCAAAGCACUGGAAUUACAGAGUAACAUCUAAUUUUAAUAUUCACAUUCCUAUUUUAAUAUUCAUAUUCGAUGAUGGCACUUAGCAACAUCCUCCUAUAUCCAUAUUAAAACCUGUUUUCCAAGAUUGUGUCUAAUAUGAAGGUGUAAAAUUGCUUUGUUUUCACUCCUUCUUGAAUGAAUAAAUUUGAUAGUAACCAA